GCAUUUCUCCCCGAGAUGGCGGGUCUGACGGCGGCGGCCCCGCGGCCCGGAGUCCUCCUGCUCCUGCUGUCCAUCCUCCACCCCUCUCGGCCUGGAGGGGUCCCUGGGGCCAUUCCUGGUGGAGUUCCUGGAGGAGUCUUUUAUCCAGGGGCUGGUCUCGGAGCCCUUGGAGGAGGAGCGCUGGGGCCUGGAGGCAAACCUCUUAAGCCAGUUCCCGGAGGGCUUGCGGGUGCUGGCCUUGGGGCAGGGCUCGGCGCCUUCCCCGCAGUUACCUUUCCGGGGGCUCUGGUGCCUGGUGGAGUGGCUGACGCUGCUGCAGCCUAUAAAGCUGCUAAGGCUGGCGCUGGGCUUGGUGGUGUCCCAGGAGUUGGUGGCUUAGGAGUGUCUGCAGGUGCGGUGGUUCCUCAGCCUGGAGCCGGAGUGAAGCCUGGGAAAGUGCCGGGUGUGGGGCUGCCAGGUGUAUACCCAGGUGGCGUGCUCCCAGGAGCUCGGUUCCCCGGUGUGGGGGUGCUCCCUGGAGUUCCCACUGGAGCAGGAGUUAAGCCCAAGGCUCCAGGUGUAGGUGGAGCUUUUGCUGGAAUCCCAGGAGUUGGACCCUUUGGGGGACCGCAACCUGGAGUCCCACUGGGGUAUCCCAUCAAGGCCCCCAAGCUGCCUGGUGGCUAUGGACUGCCCUACACCACAGGGAAACUGCCCUAUGGCUAUGGGCCCGGAGGAGUGGCUGGUGCAGCGGGCAAGGCUGGUUACCCAACAGGGACAGGGGUUGGCCCCCAGGCAGCAGCAGCAGCGGCAGCUAAAGCAGCAGCAAAGUUCGGUGCUGGAGCAGCCGGAGUCCUCCCUGGUGUUGGAGGGGCUGGUGUUCCUGGCGUGCCUGGGGCAAUUCCUGGAAUUGGAGGCAUCGCAGGCGUUGGGACUCCAGCUGCAGCUGCAGCUGCAGCAGCAGCCGCUAAGGCAGCCAAGUAUGGAGCUGCUGCAGGCUUAGUGCCUGGUGGGCCAGGCUUUGGCCCGGGAGUAGUUGGUGUCCCAGGAGCUGGCGUUCCAGGUGUUGGUGUCCCAGGAGCUGGGAUUCCAGUUGUCCCAGGUGCUGGGAUCCCAGGUGCUGCGGUUCCAGGGGUUGUGUCACCAGAAGCAGCUGCUAAGGCAGCUGCAAAGGCAGCCAAAUACGGGGCCAGGCCCGGAGUCGGAGUUGGAGGCAUUCCUACUUACGGGGUUGGAGCUGGGGGCUUUCCCGGCUUUGGUGUCGGAGUCGGAGGUAUCCCUGGAGUCGCAGGUGUCCCUGGUGUCGGAGGUGUUCCCGGAGUCGGAGGUGUCCCGGGAGUUGGCAUUUCCCCCGAAGCUCAGGCAGCAGCUGCCGCCAAGGCUGCCAAGUACGGUGCUGCAGGAGCAGGAGUGCUGGGUGGGCUAGUGCCAGGUGCCCCAGGCGCAGUCCCAGGUGUGCCGGGCACGGGAGGAGUGCCAGGAGUGGGGACCCCAGCAGCUGCAGCUGCUAAAGCAGCCGCCAAAGCCGCCCAGUUUGGGUUAGUUCCUGGUGUCGGCGUGGCUCCUGGAGUUGGCGUGGCUCCUGGUGUCGGUGUGGCUCCUGGAGUUGGCUUGGCUCCUGGAGUUGGCGUGGCUCCUGGAGUUGGUGUGGCUCCUGGCGUUGGCGUGGCUCCCGGCAUUGGCCCUGGUGGAGUUGCAGCUGCAGCAAAAUCCGCUGCCAAGGUGGCUGCCAAAGCCCAGCUCCGAGCUGCAGCUGGGCUUGGUGCUGGCAUCCCUGGACUUGGAGUUGGUGUCGGCGUCCCUGGACUUGGAGUUGGUGCUGGUGUUCCUGGACUUGGAGUUGGUGCUGGUGUUCCUGGCUUCGGGGCAGGUGCAGAUGAGGGAGUUAGGCGGAGCCUGUCCCCUGAGCUCAGGGAAGGAGAUCCCUCCUCCUCUCAGCACCUCCCCAGCACCCCCUCAUCACCCAGGGUACCUGGAGCCCUGGCUGCCGCUAAAGCAGCCAAAUAUGGAGCAGCAGUGCCUGGGGUCCUUGGAGGGCUCGGGGCUCUCGGUGGAGUAGGCAUCCCAGGCGGUGUGGUGGGAGCCGGACCCGCCGCCGCCGCUGCCGCAGCCAAAGCUGCUGCCAAAGCCGCCCAGUUUGGCCUAGUGGGAGCCGCUGGGCUCGGAGGACUCGGAGUCGGAGGGCUUGGAGUUCCAGGUGUUGGGGGCCUUGGAGGUAUACCUCCAGCUGCAGCCGCUAAAGCAGCUAAAUACGGUGCUGCUGGCCUUGGAGGUGUCCUAGGGGGUGCCGGGCAGUUCCCACUUGGAGGAGUGGCAGCAAGACCUGGCUUCGGAUUGUCUCCCAUUUUCCCAGGUGGGGCCUGCCUGGGGAAAGCUUGUGGCCGGAAGAGAAAAUGAGCUUCCUAGGACCCCUGACUCACGACCUCAUCAACGUUGGUGCUACUGCUUGGUGGAGAAUGUAAACCCUUUGUAACCCCAUCCCAUGCCCCUCCGACUCCCCACCCCAGGAGGGAACGGGCAGGCCGGGCGGCCUUGCAGAUCCACAGGGCAAGGAAACAAGAGGGGAGCGGCCAAGUGCCCCGACCAGGAGGCCCCCUACUUCAGAGGCAAGGGCCAUGUGGUCCUGGCCCCCCACCCCAUCCCUUCCCACCUAGGAGCUCCCCCUCCACACAGCCUCCAUCUCCAGGGGAACUUGGUGCUACACGCUGGUGCUCUUAUCUUCCUGGGGGGAGGGAGGAGGGAAGGGUGGCCCCUCGGGGAACCCCCUACCUGGGGCUCCUCUAAAGAUGGUGCAGACACUUCCUGGGCAGUCCCAGCUCCCCCUGCCCACCAGGACCCACCGUUGGCUGCCAUCCAGUUGGUACCCAAGCACCUGAAGCCUCAAAGCUGGAUUCGCUCUAGCAUCCCUCCUCUCCUGGGUCCACUUGGCCGUCUCCUCCCCACCGAUCGCUGUUCCCCACAUCUGGGGCGCUUUUGGGUUGGAAAACCACCCCACACUGGGAAUAGCCACCUUGCCCUUGUAGAAUCCAUCCGCCCAUCCGUCCAUUCAUCCAUCGGUCCGUCCAUCCAUGUCCCCAGUUGACCGCCCGGCACCACUAGCUGGCUGGGUGCACCCACCAUCAACCUGGUUGACCUGUCAUGGCCGCCUGUGCCCUGCCUCCACCCCCAUCCUACACUCCCCCAGGGCGUGCGGGGCUGUGCAGACUGGGGUGCCAGGCAUCUCCUCCCCACCCGGGGUGUCCCCACAUGCAGUACUGUAUACCCCCCAUCCCUCCCUCGGUCCACUGAACUUCAGAGCAGUUCCCAUUCCUGCCCCGCCCAUCUUUUUGUGUCUCGCUGUGAUAGAUCAAUAAAUAUUUUAUUUUUUGUCCUGGAUAUUUGGGGAUUAUUUUUGAUUGUUGAUAUUCUCUUUUGGUUUUAUUGUUGUGGUUCAUUGAAAAAAAAAGAUAAUUUUUUUUUCUGAUCCGGGGAGCUGUAUCCCCAGUAGAAAAAACAUUUUAAUCACUCUAAUAUAACUCUGGAUGAAACACACCUUUUUUUUUAAUAAGAAAAGAGAAUUAACUGCUUCAGAAAUGACUAAUAAAUGAAAAACCUUUAAAGGAAA